GAGCCGGAGUCGGAUGGCGGCUACGGCGGCUCAUUGUUUUCCGCUGCAGGGGUGCUGAAGGGGGGACGCGGGUCGGACGCGUCCGGCUGUGGAAGAGAGCGGCGGCCGCUCACAACAUGCACAGCCUGGCGACGGCUGCGCCUGUGCCUACUACACUGGCACAAGUGGAUAGAGAAAAGAUCUAUCAGUGGAUCAAUGAGCUGUCCAGUCCUGAGACUAGGGAAAAUGCUUUGCUGGAGCUAAGUAAGAAGCGAGAAUCUGUUCCUGACCUUGCACCCAUGCUGUGGCAUUCAUUUGGUACUAUUGCAGCACUUUUACAGGAAAUUGUAAAUAUUUAUCCAUCUAUCAACCCACCCACCUUGACAGCACACCAGUCUAACAGAGUUUGCAAUGCUCUGGCAUUACUGCAAUGUGUAGCAUCACAUCCAGAAACCAGGUCAGCGUUUCUCGCAGCACACAUCCCACUUUUUUUGUACCCCUUUUUGCACACUGUCAGCAAAACACGUCCCUUUGAGUAUCUCCGGCUCACCAGCCUUGGAGUUAUUGUAGAGACGGGGUUUCACCAUGUUGGCCAGGCUGAUCUUGAACUCCCGACCUCAAGUGAUCUGCCCGCCUCGGCCUCCCAAAGUGCUGGGAUUACAGGGGCCCUGGUGAAAACAGAUGAACAAGAAGUAAUCAACUUUUUAUUAACAACAGAAAUUAUCCCUUUAUGUUUGCGAAUUAUGGAAUCUGGAAGUGAACUUUCUAAAACAGUUGCCACAUUCAUCCUCCAGAAGAUCUUGUUAGAUGACACUGGUUUGGCUUAUAUAUGUCAGACGUAUGAGCGUUUCUCCCAUGUUGCCAUGAUCUUGGGUAAGAUGGUCCUGCAGCUAUCCAAAGAGCCUUCUGCCCGUCUGCUGAAGCAUGUAGUGAGAUGUUACCUUCGACUUUCAGAUAACCCCAGGGCACGUGAAGCACUCAGACAGUGCCUCCCUGACCAGCUGAAAGACACAACCUUCGCCCAGGUGCUAAAAGAUGACACCACCACGAAACGCUGGCUUGCACAACUGGUGAAGAACCUGCAAGAGGGCCAGGUCACCGAUCCCCGGGGUAUCCCCCUGCCCCCUCAGUGAUCCUUCCCUGUUCCCUCCCACUACUCCCCCAAGUUGGGGAAAGGAGGGGGAACCUACGAGAAAAACAGCUCAGGUUUUAUCACCGACUGGGAAUAGACAACCUCAAUGCUGAACCGCACUGGAGAAAAGGGGCAAGGUACCCCUGCUGAGGUGUAUGGGCUGCCAUCUCAGGCUGUCUUGAGGACCUGGGCUCCCUCUGCUACUCCCAGGAAAUGGGCUCCUGACACAGCAGUCUGCCACCACAGCCCCAGGAGGGUGUCAACACCAGCAAAUGCUGUAUUUGCAGCAUGUCCAAGAUGACCCUUCUCCCCUACCUCUACCUAGCCACUGGCAGGGAGGGGAGACAGUGGUGAUAGCAGCAGCACUCUAGGCAUGGUGAACGCCUGGGACCAAGCCAUGUGGCGUUUUUUAUUUUGCCUUUCUGGAAGACUCAAGAUAUGUCUCUUCAUUCUCUCUCAGUAUUUGUUUACUUUGGUUUUUUUGUUUUUAAUCUCAGAGAGAGGUGUGUUUAGUGGGCACAAGCUGUAAUAUUCAGCAAAACUUUGUCGACUGGCACUGUUUACAAGUCUGUUAGCUGCAUAAGCUCAAUAAAAAGUUGGUCUGGGCAUUACAUCCCCUCUGGCAGGCCAAUAGCUGCAUCAAGCUGUUGGGAGAAAUGGGAGGGCAGGGGAAAGAUGUAAAGCCAAAGUACAGCAGGAACCCACCACCUGUUUCCCUUCCUUCUCCCAUUCUACUCCCAGUCCGGAAUGCCACGAGGACCUUAACCUUGUUUCUGGCUUUAGCUGCUAGUUUUCCCAAAUCUCAGUGCUUUCCCUUUUUGAACUUCCCUUCUAUUAAACUUAAAACAGAUGUCUUAAUUAAUCAGGCUGUCUUGGAAGGGUAUUGUAUUGGGAGACAAGGGGCGGUGGUGGACCUCACCUUCAAUCCAAGUUUUCAAAGAUAUUUUCUCAAUAACUCUAAAAGGGAGGUGCUUGGGAUUAAGGUGACAGUCCACUUGAUCCUUUUCUUUGUUUUAGUGUGAAUUUCAGCAGCUCCAUCUGUCUUCAUGAUUGUACUUGAGCAGUAUUAGCUGUAUGAGUUAAUUUUAUUCAGAUUGAAGAUGGAGGGCUGGGUUCUGCUCACUCAGUCUUUUUUUUUUUUUUUUUUUUUUUUUUUUGACCAUUCUCUUUUAGUCUAUGGGAAUUACAGGGUUGCCGCUAAAAUAUUCACUUGUUCAUAUCGUGUCAGAGAUUUCCUCUUCUCUGGAGCUUAGGUGGCUCUUCACAAUCCAUAGGCUUGAAUCUGCAACCUAGUGUAAACUGCCUUGCUUUCCCCGGUUCUUUCCCCUGCUAGCACCUGCUUUCUCAUCCCUAUCUCCAGUCAAAGAUGGGAUUGCUUAAUCCAACUCUGGAGAGGGACCAAGUCUUUUCUGCCCACAUCUCACACAAUUGAGGUGUCUGAACAAGCUUGGGGAGGGUCUAUAAGGGGUAGGCUCAAAAAAAAAAAAACCCAUUUGCAGAGGCAGUUUUGCCAACACAAGGGCUCUUUCAAGCCGACUUUCACAAAGAGAGCCGGACUUGUUAGUUGGCUUCUGUCUCUUUAGAGCCAAGAAAAUAGUAAUUAAGUGGCCUAGAUAUAGGAAGGGCAGAAUAAGCACUUACUCCCCCUGCCUUCCAAGAUGAAGAGGAGAAGCAGGCCAACCCUCAAUAAUUGCAAGCCUGAAGAGAAGUGAUCUUAGAGAAAGCAGAGAACAGAAUGGACUGGAUAGACAUCUUGACUCUAUUCAGCCCGUAGUCUGUGAUCUGGAGAGUCCAGUUAAGGUAACCCAGAUUUUUGACAACCGCCUUCCUGCUGAGCCAAAGUUUUCUCAUUACCCCUCCACUGGGGAAGCAGCUGAGGCCCAGGGCCUUGCUCCCUGGGAAAUUCUCUUCUCUCCAUCUUUCGGUGCAUUGGCCAUGUUACUGUGCCAAAGUGUCUUAAUUCUUGUCCCAUCUAUUCUCAGCUGGCCUUGGAACCCACAUAGGAGUUGGUGGGGGAGGGAUGGAAUGGGUAUUAUUCAUUGUAGUUGAUCCUGGUGUGUGUAUUAUAUAAAGAGACCCCUCCCCUUAUUUUGUGUUUUCCAUCCCUCUCCCUUAACAGGAUUGAAAUAAAACAUGCUUCUGUUUUUGUAAAAAUAAUUUUUCCUUUACACUGGAGAUUUUAUUCUAUCAGUAUAUGGGUAACUAGGCACUUUGGUCAGGUGAUCCUUGUCAUGCCUGCUUCUCCCCUCUGUCUACCUACACAACACACACACACACACACACACAGCCCUGCUAAGAUGGCAGUAGUGGUUCUUUUGUGAACAUGUUUUUUGGGGAGACUCCAUCUGAGGUACAAAAGCUGUUUGGGAGGCUGGGAGGGGGAUGAUGCCCCUUACCUGAUAAAAGUAUGUUUUACUGGGACAGAACUUCACUCCUGGCCAUAUUGGCCAGAACUUAGUGCCAGUGUAGGGAGAGACUUCCAUAGUGACAAGGUAAUGCUUGAAACAUCUUACGAACUUUGAUGUUCAUUUCCUCAAGUUCAAGGCUUGGAGCACAUCUCCAGGAUUGUUUCCAUGCCUGGCUGUCAGUGGGACACAGCUGCCCUAUGCUUCCACGUUCUUUUUUCAAGAGCCUUAGAGGGCCUGUGGCCUGUUUCACUGGUGGAACAGGAGCAGCAUUGGUAGCCUUCAGAGCAUGCCUUGCUUACUAACUACAUAUUAUUCCUCUGCUCAUUGUUCCUGCUGCUUAAAGGCUAGGAAAAGGGGGAUAUACAAAGUUGUUGCUUUCAAAAACUCAGAGAAAAAA